GUCGUUCGUGUCUGUUGAACGGCUGUGGGCGUCUUGCUGCCUUGGGUAGGGGGUUAAAAUCGUUCUUGAGAGGAACGUCUCUGUGCGAAGAGAUAAUGAGUUUAGCUCUGAGAAGUGAGCUUGUAGUGGACAAAACAAAGAGGAAAAAAAGAAGAGAACUGUCUGAGGAACAGAAACAAGAAAUUAAAGAUGCUUUUGAACUAUUUGAUACAGACAAAGAUGAAGCAAUAGAUUAUCAUGAAUUAAAGGUGGCAAUGAGAGCCUUGGGGUUUGAUGUAAAAAAAGCUGAUGUACUGAAGAUUCUUAAAGAUUAUGACAGAGAAGCCACAGGGAAAAUCACCUUUGAAGAUUUUAAUGAAGUUGUGACAGACUGGAUAUUGGAAAGAGAUCCCCAUGAAGAAAUACUCAAGGCAUUUAAACUAUUUGAUGAUGAUGAUUCAGGUAAAAUAAGCUUGAGGAAUUUGCGACGUGUUGCUAGAGAAUUGGGUGAAAACAUGAGUGAUGAAGAACUUCGAGCUAUGAUAGAAGAAUUUGACAAAGAUGGUGAUGGAGAAAUUCUUAAGAACAUACUCUUGCUUCCUAUUUGGUCUAGAUGCCUCAGUCUAAAUCGGGAGUUCUUCAGUGAAGUAAACCAAGAGGAGUUCAUUGCUAUUAUGACUGGUGACAUUUAAAGAAUUACAAGGAUAAACACUAAGAAUGUUGCAGUUACCAUCUUAUAUUCUAUUUUUGUGCCUGGAGCCAUGUGAAAAAAACCAACUUAGUUCUUUUAUCCUAAAGGACCAAAAAUAAGCAUCUUAUAUAUCUGUAUUUUACUACUGUUAAGUUUCUUUGUAUGAACUGUGUUGUUAGUACUCAGAUAGUUUAGCUUUGUAUUUAUAAUAGAGCUUUUAUAUAAAGUUUUAAAAAUUGAAUGUGUGAUAUGUGUUCUUUGAAGGUUUUUUAAUUUAACAUUUAUAGUCACUUUUUAGUGCACACAUUUUCCAGACUUUCGUUAAUAAAAUAUUUAUUUUAUUAGAAUUUUAAAGUUUGGUAAAUUUGUUUUUAUUCCUAGUAUCUGUUAACCCUCAAGAGUGGAUUUCUUAAAUCUUCCCUUUAUAAUUUUACUAGUUUCUGAAACAAAAAUUGAAAUACAAUUAGCAAUAGAGUGGCACAUUUUUCCAUUACCUAACAUUUCAUCAAUUUUGACAUUCUAUAUUUUAAUACAAGCUGACUCAAUAUAAGCCUAAUUCCUUUUUUAAGAGUCCUGUCUUUGAGUUUAGAAGGAAUAAGUAUUGUGCAGAUAGACCCAUUUAUCCUUGUGUAUUAUGUUUCUUAACUUGGUAUCAUUGUAAGUAUGAAAGUUAAUUUUCUUCUGAAUAUUUCCUUAAACAAAUUGAAUGAAUACAAUUUGAAUUUUCUAACUUCUUGACUGAGAGAUUUAAAUUUUGGAAUUUUGAUUUGUUAAGGUAAUUAUCACUCAAUUACAUGUCACAGUGAUGAAAAUAGAAAACUGUAAGCCACAGAAAUAAUUUAAGUCUAUGUUUUACCUAUAUGAAGGAACAGUCUGUGAUUCACCAGGAAAUAGUAGAGACACAGUUUCCAAGUACUGGUGGGCUCUUCUGCCUUGUAGAAGUGUAUGUUAGGGGGAAACAAGUGGUUAUGGAGAUCGAUCAUAGAAAAAAAUAGUACCUAUAUGGAUCCUUCACUCAUAUCUAGUACUCGGUGUUAUGGGCUCUCCCAGGAACGGAAUUGAGUUGUCUAUUUCAGCAAUCUUUCUUUAGAAUUCUUGUUUUAAAUUUUUAAGUUUAAAGUGUAGUAUCAUUUGAGGCGCUUUAAAUGUUGUGAGCCUUUUAAGAGUAUUACAUUAAGGGUUGUCCACUAGAAAUUUAACACAAAAUCAGUAGGGAAUACUAUAGCAGUAGUGACAUUUCAAACAGUUAUCUAGGAAGCAAGUGUAUAUUAAGUCAUUCUUGUAUUGCUACGAAGAAAUACCCAAGACUGCAUAUUUUAUAAAGAAAAGAAGCUUAAUUGGCUUACGGUUCUGCAGGCUUUACAGGAAGCAUGGUGCUUCUGCUUUUGGGGAGGCCUCAGGAAGCUUACAGUCAUGGUAGAAGGCAAAGGGGGAGCAGGCACAUCACAUGGUGAAAACCAGAGUGAACAAGUGAGAGAAGUGCCAAGUACUUUGAAACCACCAGAUCUCAUGAGAACUCACUAUUGUGAGGACAUCUAAUCACCUCCCACCAGACCUCACCUCCAGUACUGGGGAUUACAAUUCAACAUGAUAUUUGAGUGGGGACAGAUAUACAAACUAUAUCAGCAGGUUAACUAGAGUAAAACUUAAUUUUGAAUACAAAUUCAAUGGUCACAGUCAUUAUAUUCAGGGCAACAGACCUUGAAAUUAAAAAAUUUUUGUCGCACACUGAUGAGUUCCCUCUGUCUUGAUCAUGAAAUAUAUUGAUUUCCAGGAAAGUGAAAAAUAAAACAGUAAAAGUAAAUCUA